UUUCAGGGGUCUUGUGAGGAGCAGAAUAAAUAAAGUGCUUAGGAUGGACUAAAGAAUUGGAAACAACCCGAAUGCAUCACUCGAGUAUUGAUUAAGAAACUAGAGCAUAUCCAUACCGCGGAAGCUCAUAGUGCCGCUAAUGUCUGUGCAGUAAGGUCUCAUUUAUGUAGAAACACAUCAAGCACCUUUUCUCCCCGCUAUGGAUGACUUUUUUAGUAAAAGCACAGGAAAAGGUCUGGGACGUCAUUUGUCAGACUGUUAAGUCGGGGGGUACAAUGGUAUUGAGGAAGGGAGAGUUUUACAGAUUUCUAUAUUGUUUGAAUCUUCCCUUUUUUAUUAAGAUGGUUUGUAUUUUUUUCAUUUUCUUUUUACUUUUCUUUUCUUUCUUUUUUUUUUUUUUUUGAGAUGGUCUCACUCUGUUGCCCAGGCUGGAGUACAGUGGUGCGAUCAUAGCUCAUUGCAACCUCAAACUCCUGGACUCAAGCAAUCUUUCCUCCUCAGCCUCCCCAGUAGCUGGGACUACAGGAGCCCCACCUGGCUUUUUUUGUUUUUUGGUACAGAUGGCGUCUCACAUUGUCUUCCCAAAGGGGUCUUGAACCCCUGGCCUCAAGCAAUCAUCCUGUGUCUGUCUCCCAAAAUGCUGGGAUUACAGGCAUAAGCCACCAAGCCCGGCCAGUUUGUAUUUUUAUUGUUGAAACAAAAAAUCGAUUACUGAAAAUUGCAUAAUACACUUUUCAGUAGAGAGUAACAAUGUAAGGUAUAAAUGUGUCAUACAUUUAUAUGUACCUGUGGAUAAAUGGCUUUGGAUGGUGUCUGUAAGCCCUUCUGUGACACCUCAGGGCCAGAUGUGUUUUGGAAUUCAGAGGUUUUCAAAUUUGAGAAAGAUAAUAUAGUGCACAGACGAUAUAUCAAGCACAUCUCCAGAGGGAUCUGGGGCAACACUAAAUAAUGAAACAUAUCAGUUAAAAUUUUUUAAUUAGGCCGGGCGCAGUGGCUCACGCCUGUAAUCCCAGCACUUUAGGAGGCCGAGGCGGGUGGAUCACAAGGUCAGGAGUUUGAGACCAUCCUGGCCAACAUGGUGAAACCUCGUCUCUACUAAAAAUACAAAAAAUUAGCUGGACGUGGUAGCUGGUGCCUGUAGUCCCAGCUACUUGGGAGGCUGAAGCAGGAGAAUCGCUUGAACCUGGCAGGCAGAGGUUGCAGUGAACUGAGAUUGCGCCACUGCACUCCAGCCUGGGCGACAGAGUGAGACUCUCUCUCAGUAAAAAAAAAAAAAAAAGAUAUUUAAUUGAUGUAUAAUGUGCAAUACAGAAAAACACACGAGUGGGUAUAGCUCAAUGAAAUUUUAUAAACUGAAGAUAUAUGUUAUUAAUAUUUCCACCAUAAUUUUGAACAUUUACAUUUAGUGGAAUAAAUUGAGAUUAUAAAUAUGCUUAUAUCAGGUCAGGUGGUGCUGCCAAAUGAAUGACAUUGGGUUUUGCUGUCAAAGAGUUAUGAAACACCCGGGUUUUGGAUUUCUGGCUUUGGGAUGAGAGCUUGUGGGCCUGUGUUAAUAGGAGAGACAGUCACAUGAGCAAGGCAUUACAGUAAAGCCUAGAAAAGGCUUCAGGGCCAUGAAAGGAUGGGGACUGGAUGGCUCUUCAGCCUGGGGUUUGCUCGUGUAUUCCACAUCCUUCCUCCUCAGUCCUGCCAUUUUGCUCUUUCCCCAGGAGUACACAUCCAGAUGCCAGCCCAGCUACCACAGGGGAUCCCUCUGGGAGACUGAAAGUACAGGUUCUGGGGCCCAGGUUGAAGCCGACCAACCCUGAGCCUCAGGCCAGGGGAAUGGCAGCCCCCUUGGAGGCCCAGGACCAGGCCCCUGGGGAGGGAGAAGGGCUUCUGAUUGUGAAAGUGGAAGAUUCCUCCUGGGAACAGGAAUCUGCCCAGCAUGAGGAUGGCAGGGAUUCCGAAGCCUGCCGCCAGCGCUUCCGGCAAUUCUGCUACGGGGAUGUGCAUGGGCCUCAUGAGGCCUUCAGCCAGCUCUGGGAGCUCUGCUGCCGCUGGCUGCGGCCCGAGCUGCGUACCAAGGAGCAGAUCCUGGAGCUGCUGGUGCUGGAGCAGUUCCUGACAGUGCUGCCAGGGGAGAUCCAGGGCUGGGUGCGUGAGCAGCACCCGGGAAGCGGUGAGGAGGCUGUCGCCUUGGUGGAGGACCUACAGAAGCAGCCAGUGAAAGCCUGGCGACAGGAUGUGCCCUCGGAGGAGGCGGAACCCGAGGCUGCAGGCCGGGGAUCCCAGGCCACGGGGCCUCCCCCGACGGUGGGGGCACGGAGGCGGCCGUCUGUUCCCCAGGAGCAGCACAGCCAUAGCGCCCAGCCUCCUGCUCUUCUUAAAGAGGGUCGUCCCGGAGAGACGACGGACACCUGCUUUGUCUCUGGGGUCCAUGGACCUGUGGCAUUGGGAGACAUCCCAUUCUAUUUCUCCCGGGAAGAAUGGGGCACCCUGGACCCUGCUCAGCGGGAUCUCUUCUGGGACAUAAAGCGGGAGAACUCCCGGAACACCACCCUGGCUCUGGCCCCAGAACCGCGUGGGACUGAAGAGGUCGCCUCCUUCCCCUUGCAGGUUUUGGGCUCAAAGGCCAAAGUGAGAAGUCCCUGCUGCAGGAGAUGGUGCCGGUGGUGCCAGGCCAGACAGGCAGCGACGUGACUGUGUCCUGGAGCCCCGAGGAGGCUGAGGCCUGGGAGAGCGAGAACCGGCCGAGGGCGGCCCUGGGCCCAGUGGUGGGCGCGCGACGGGGGCGGCCACCCACUCGCCGGCGCCAGUUCCGGGACCUGGCAGCCGAGAAGCCGCACAGCUGCGGGCAGUGUGGAAAGCGCUUCCGCUGGGGCUCGGACCUGGCGCGGCACCAGCGCACGCACACGGGCGAGAAGCCACACAAGUGCCCUGAGUGCGACAAGAGCUUCCGCAGCUCCUCGGACCUGGUGCGCCACCAAGGCGUGCACACGGGCGAGAAGCCCUUCUCCUGUUCCGAGUGCGGCAAGAGCUUCAGCCGCAGCGCCUACCUGGCCGACCACCAGCGCAUACACACGGGCGAGAAGCCUUUCGGCUGCAGCGACUGCGGCAAGAGCUUCUCGCUGCGCUCCUACCUGCUGGACCAUCGGCGUGUGCACACCGGUGAGCGGCCCUUCGGCUGCGGAGAGUGCGACAAGAGCUUCAAGCAGCGCGCGCACCUCAUCGCGCAUCAGAGCCUGCACGCCAAGAUGGCCCAGCCCGUGGGGUGAGCAGCUGGCUUGGCCGGAAACCCGGGGGAGGCCCAGCCACGGCACAUCCUGCUUUGUUCACCACUGGGACUCUCCUUCCAUCUGUGGCCACCUCCCGGGCUGUCCGAGGGACCCCAGGGUACCUCACACUCGGAGCUCGCCUGCCCUGCUUGGCUCUGAGGACCUGCCCAGCGCUCAAAGGGAACGGAAGCCUUCCCCUCCCGCCCCCGAUCUUGUCCUCUUUCCCCCUUCUGCGCCUAGCGUUCCUCUUCCCCUCUAGUUUCCUGGAGCCCCAACACAUUCCUGGCAGGGACAGCAGGGUGGCAAGGACUCAGGUCUAGGUCCCUUCCCAGAAGCCCCCGAGCCUCAUUUGACUGUGUGGCUCUUUGGCCCCCACCCUGUGGGGUGGGUCCAUGGGUCAGGCCUCUGCCCUACCAACCUGUGCCUUUCAGUGGGCGUGGAGGACUGGCCUUGGCCCCCCAGGGGGCUGCUGGACUUUGGGAGAGACAGCCCACACCUGUGGGACCGCGGGUCUUAGUCACGGCGGCAGGGGCUUUCUGGCCCCCUCCCACUCCCGUUUCCAGGCCAUGACCACUCUGCCCUGUCCUGGCCAUACGGACUCGGCCUGCCUUUGCCCUCGGCCUACUUGCCCUAGCAUGAGGCUCUGAGAGCCACCUGCCCACCAAUCUGGUGAGGAUAAUGGUGGCUCCAGCGACAGGAGGCCAACCCUGGAGACCAAGAACAGGGCGCCUGGCUGCCAUCUUUUCCUCCAGAGGUGGGGCUGCACCAGACUCAGCACUAGCACUCCAUCAGCACUAGCACCUCACUCCAUCAGCACUAGCACCUCACUCCAUCGGCCCCGGCACCCUGCUCCAUCGGCACUGGCGCCCUGCUCCAUCGGCACUAAUGCUCCACUCGGCGCCCCACUCCAUCGGCCCCGCUCCAUCGGCACUAAUGCCCCACUCGGCGCCCCACUCCAUCAGCACUAAUGCUCCACUCCAUUGGCACUAACGCCCCAACUCCAGCGGCACUAAUGACCCGCUCCUUUGACAUUGGUGCCCCACUCCAUCAGCACUAACGCCCUGCUCCAUCGGCACUGGUGUCCCACUCCAUUGUCACUAACGUCCGGCUCCAUCGGCACUACCACCCCGCUCCAUCAUCACUAUGUCCAGCUCCGUCGGCACUACCACCCUGCUCCAUCAUCACUACGUCCAGCUCCAACGGCACUGGUGCCCCAUUCCAUCGGCACUAACGCCCCGCUCCACCGGCACCAGUGCCUCGCUCCAUUGGCACCAACGCCCAGCUCCACCGGUACUGGCUCCCUGCUCCAUCGGCACUAACGCCCUGCUUCAUUGGCACUUUGCUGCUGCCUCCUGAGCACUGCCUUCCAUGAACAGGGACAGACCAGAGGCCCUGCAAGGACUCCCCCUCAGACCUCCAAAGGGCAACAGAAGAGUAUUAAUAAACGUGAAAACUUA